GGAGAUGAGGGAGCGGCCGGAGAAGAGAGGAUGCUGUUGAGCGUUAGGUCGCGACCCCUGCUGGAAGGUGCUGUUUCUCCCUCCUUUCUGGGGCUGGGAAUGGGGGGAUGUGGGCUGCAUCCAAGUCGCUGCCCCCCACGCCCUUCCAACCUCCGUCACAGCUAUUCUCGGCCAGUUUGCGCGGGGACUUGCUGAUCUCCCUUCAGCCGGCCCCGGGGUCUGCGGGAGGGGACUGGGUGGGGAGGGAGACUUAAGGGCGCUGGCGGCUGUCGUUCCGGUCGCUGAGAGUCUGCCCCACAGCUCCAGUUUUUCCAAGUUAAGAGAUAUGGAGAUUUCCACAAGGAUUUGGAGAGGAGCCCCAGUAGUUACUAAAAUUCUGCAUUAGAUCUGUCAGGAAAGCUUCCCCUAACUGAAAGCUGGAUGAUGACCCGAAGGACCAGUGAGACUGCAGCUUCCGGAACUCAUUCACAGCAGUAAUAAUAGAUGGACUUCAAGGCAAUUGCCCAACAAACUGCCCAAGAAGUUUUAGGUUAUAAUCGAGAUACAUCAGGCUGGAAAGUGGUUAAAACUUCACUAAUUAUUUGUGGAUUUUUAUUCCCCUUUGAGAAAAAGAUAACUGUUUCCAGUAAGGCUUCUAGAAAAUUCCAUGGAAAUCUAUAUCGUGUUGAAGGGAUAAUUCCAGAAUCACCAGCUAAACUAUCUGAUUUCCUCUACCAAACUGGAGACAGAAUUACAUGGGAUAAAUCAUUGCAAGUGUAUAAUAUGGUACACAGGAUUGAUUCGGACACAUUCAUAUGUCAUACCAUUACACAAAGUUUUGCCGUGGGCUCCAUUUCCCCUCGAGACUUUAUCGACUUAGUGUACAUCAAGCGCUACGAAGGAAAUAUGAACAUUAUCAGUUCUAAAAGUGUGGAUUUUCCAGAAUAUCCUCCAUCUUCAAAUUAUAUCCGCGGUUAUAACCAUCCUUGUGGCUUUGUAUGUUCACCAAUGGAAGAAAACCCAGCAUAUUCCAAACUAGUGAUGUUUGUCCAGACAGAAAUGAGAGGAAAAUUGUCCCCAUCAAUAAUUGAAAAAACCAUGCCUUCCAACUUAGUAAACUUCAUCCUCAAUGCAAAAGAUGGAAUAAAGGCACACAGAACUCCAUCAAGACGUGGAUUUCAUCAUAAUAGUCAUUCAUGAUACCAAAAGAAGAAAUGAGGCCGUUCUGCUAUAAAAUCAUGUGUAGUAGUUAUUGCUGUUUACUUCUAAGUCAACGCACAUAAAUAAUACUGUUAAACUAUUCUAGACAGUAUUCUUGUACACAUGGCUGAAGAUAGUUCAUAAAAAUAAGAACUCAUAGUUGUACAAGAAUAUGGCAUUAAAUACCGUUUUUAAUCUCA